CUUUCCCCGCAGGGCUGGGGGUCCGCUGUUUCCCCGCGCUGCUGCCGAGGCCCCGCCGUCCGCGUCCUGGCCGUGUGUCCACACCCCAGACUGCGGGCCGGGGCGCACUCUGUCUUCUUGCGCGGAGCGUCGGAGGCCUGAGGUCAGGGCGGCUCGGGCGGGUCCAGCCCCGCGGACCGCGCCCACCCGAGGGUGGCCUGGGCAGGGACCUGGGGGUCCUGGGAGCGGAGUGUGAGCCGAGUGCAGGUGGCUCCCCGGGCAGGUCCUUCUCCUACAAGGCAGUAGUGUCUGUCGCCGGCCGGGCCGCGUUGGAUUCCGCGGCCCGCGGGAGCAUGGCCUCCAGGCCCCUCUUCCUGCGGCUGCUCUGCCCGGGAGCACGGGGCGCCCUUCAUCCCGGAGCUGGAGCUUCCUCACCCCAGGAUGCCCCAUCACUUCUGUCCCGAAGAGGGGCUGGGAUCUUCUUGGGAAGACCAGCCCCCAACAGAGGCUGCUCCCUGGGUCCCCCGACUCCAGGCCUCAGGACUCCACGGCUCCAAGGGCCUGCCCCGGCCCAGGCCUGGGGACCACUGAGCCCCACACUGGUCUUUGCUGGCCUCUGUCCACCUCCCGGUAGCUGUGUGUCUCCCACAGCUGCCCAGAGAUGGGGCCUGCGGUGCCUAUGCAGCCUCCCCGCUGUGCCCGAAGUGCUGACCCGCCAGCCCCAUGGACACCAGGCUUGGAGUCUAGGCAGGAGCCUGGCACCCCCUCCACGUUCUGGGUCUUCCUGGCGGCAGCCAUGCUGCCCGUGCUGGGCCACCCUCGGGCCCCCUUUGGCCCCAUGCAGUAGUGACGCAAGGCCUCCUGUGUCCCCUCCUGGCCCUGCACUGCUACAGGCAGAAGCAACUGGAGAACUAUGGCUCGGGUCUCGCUAAGGUGCAGCAUCACAAACUCCAGGACUCUUGAAGCAAGCAUGGGGAGGACCCGUGAUCCUGGCGGCCUGGGCUACCUGUCCGGGCCUAAGUCGCCUCUGCCCCCUCUCCUGGCUUGCUCUGGGGUCCAGGGCCUGGGCCUCUCUGGCUGAGAAACUAGGAAGUCACUGGGCUCUGUUUCCUGAGCUGGGUAUACCAAGGCCAGUCCUAUAGGGCAGGGGUCCCCAACCCCCAGGUGCAGACCAGUACCAGCUUGUGGCCCGUUAGGAACCGGGCAGCACAGGACGAGGUGAGGGAGCAUGAUUGCCCGAGCUCCACCCACUUUCAGAUCAGCCUGGGCAUCAGAUUCCCAUAGGAGCGUGAACCCUACUGUGAGCUGCGCACUUGGAUCUGGAUUGCGCUCUGGUGAGAAUCUAAUGCCUGAUGAACUGAGGUGGAAUAGUUUCAUCCCGAAACCUUCCUCCCCAACACGGAAAAACUGUCCUCCGUGAAACCUGUCCCAGGCGCCAAAAAGGUUAGGUACUUGCUGUAGGGCCACCUGAUCUUUUCUCCAGCUUCUGUGAGGUUGGCUGGCAGUCCCUGAAGACUCCUGCCUGAGGCCUCUGCCUGAACCCUGUCCUCAGGGGGCCAGAAGCAAACUCCAGCCCUCCCCGUGUCUACUGCUCGCUGAGGAAGCCGCAGGUGCACACUGGAUCCACAAGGCACAGAACCAUCUUGGCCCUCGGCAAGCCCCCGCUUCCGCCAGGGCAGACGGCCUCAGGUGACAAUGGGUUUUCCCUUCACUGGAGUUUAAAAUAAUCCAGACUCCUCAGCAACUCCUGCUUCCAGAAUCAAAAAUAAGUGUCUCUGGGGCCCAAGGUAGGGGGUGAGGGGGACAUACCAGCAGCUUCCACCAGAGGUGGGGCGGGGCAGGGCACCAGCAGAGAAAACAUGCGGGCAAACACACACGGCCUGGGGAAAACCCCCUGAAGCCAAUGGAGACUUGCCUUUGCUCAAGGCCUUUCCUGAGAGCUUAGUGGUGGGACGGGUCCCACCUGGCUCAGCACACCGCCCGCAGGGGCCUCUGCAGCUGUCAGGUCAGCUGUGGGUGCAGAAGCCGAUACUCCCCCGGCUCAGGCUUGCUGCUAUCUUUAGCACUGUGCUCAGACUCCAGUGGCCUGGGAACCCUCUGCAGGGGGCUCUGCAGCCCUUCUCACAUUCCCGGUGGCCUCGGGGGGCCUCCCAACCAUGCUUCCCCCCUCGGUGUGGUUCUCCCCACUCCUGCAGCCCAGCAGUGCCCCUUCAGGAUCACACCCAGACCCCACUGGACUGGCAGCAGGGGAUGCCCUGGCCCUUGCUCCCAGCCCCAGGGUUCCACAUCUGGUCACCUGACACCUUGCAGUCGGCCCCAGGUCCCUCCUGGGCAGGUCAUGCCUCCAGGGUCCUCAACCUCAGGAGUCAGUGCUUCAUAGAGGCCGCUGGACCUGGGGAUGGCACCAGGCAGCAUCUCAGGGGACGCCAACUGUGACCAUGUGUCCCUCAGGGGGUAGGACCUCUGCUCAAGAGACAUGCAAGUGGCACCUGUCUUUUUAGCCUUGCAGACACGGUGGCGCCCCCAGGGAUCCCACCUGCUGUUGUGGCUGCAUAUAGUCACUCCCACCACUGCCCCUGCAGCACCGAGGGGCAGGUGCCCUGGGUCCUGUUACCUACUGCGUCCCACGCAGACGCAGGCCUGGGGGGCUCCAAAAGCUUGUUCUCCACUCAGCCUGUAGGCCUCCUCCUUGAUCCUGCUUGGCCUGCAGACCCUCCUCCCACCCCUUGAACCAGGGCAUCUGGAUGCUGACUCUGUGGUGGCCUCUGAUGUCUGACACCACCAACAGACCCUGGGCCAGGUCCCUACCCCAGACUCUGUGCCUGAGGCCAUGGUAUAGUGGGGAAGACCAGGCUCAGGGCCCUAGAGUCCCCCUCCCAGCCCAUCUGAGCAACGUGGCCAUCUCCAUGGCUCCUCCAACCCAGAAAUGUCAUCACCCAUGGGCCAGGCAAGGAGCUCCCAGCCAUGAGGUCAGACGGGGUGGUCCCAGGGCCAAGGCUAUGGACUGACUUCUGUCACCAAGGCAGGGAGGGGCGUGGACACCCCUGACAGACAGAGUGUGCUUGGCAGAAGCCCGGUGACCAGCUGCAGUCACCCACAGCAGCGUUGUGCAAAUCUAGAAAAAGUGCCCCUUCCUCUGGCUCCUGCAGUUCCAGGGUGCCCAGGCCCCCAGCCAAGAGCGUGUACAGGUGGCCCUGCUGACACACAGAAUCCUUGGGAGAACAAAGCCUCCCCGGGGUUCGGGGACAGGUGGAUGGGAGGUAGUCCUGGCCAGAGGUAUCUGGGGAGGCUGGGGGCCUUGCGGGGUGAGGCAGGGCAAGGGUGUGAGUCACUGCCAGGCUGCCAAAGCUCACUCUGCAGCUGUCCAGUCCCCUGGGGUAGCCCCAAGCCUGUCCUUGUAGGGAGUGGCAGCCGGAGUCUGAACUGUCCUGGGGGACCAAGCAGGAGCUUAAGAUGGGCAAGACCUGGGGCCCUGGGCAGACGCAUCAAAGCAGGCAGAAGCAGGCAUGGUGAGCAGGCCGCCGUGCAUGCCUGGGGCAGGCGUGUGGGUGUGAGCUGUGCUGUGCAUGUGUACAUGCGCACAGACGAGCGUGGGCGUGUCCGUGCUUGCGUGUGAAUGCAGGUGUGGGCGUGUGCUCUGCCUGCAUAUGUGUGUGCAUGAGCGUGUGUAUGUGCGUGUGUGUGACCUUGCGGGUGUGGGCUGUGCUGUGUUGUGGGAAGUACGUGCCUCACGUUGCUCUCCUGGUGAGAGUCCGGAGCAGGAUGAGGGGGUUCCUGGCUUUCACAAAAUCCCGGUACCCAGAACAAGCCCACCCAGAGUCCACUUGCCCCUCAAGCCUUCAGAGGCCAAGCUGGCUCCUGCUGGACGGCGAUCCCUGACCACUGUGCUCUGUGGGCCUUCUGGAAGCCACUGUCCCUCCCCCAGUCCCUGUGCUGAAGCCAGACACCUGCAGCCGUCCUGCCCCCAACCCCAGCUACCCAGGCCUGAGGCUGGCAUGCUCCUCAGCUGUCUGGCCCCCUCCAGCCCGAAGGGCUGAGGUCCACCCUUCAUCUGAGUUAAGUCUCUCAAAACUCUGGGUGCCCUGGAGGGUUUCGUCAGCCAGCCCAGGACCCUCAGCCAUGGUGCUCCCACCGCAGGCCAGCAGGAAGACCAAGAAGAAGGAAGGGGGUGCCCUCCGGGCCCAGAGAGCCUCAUCCAAUGUCUUCUCCAACUUUGAGCAGACUCAGAUCCAGGAGUUCAAGGAGGCAUUCACACUCAUGGAUCAGAACCGAGAUGGCUUCAUUGACAAGGAGGACCUGAAGGACACCUAUGCCUCCCUGGGCAAGACCAACGUCAAGGACGACGAGCUGGACGCCAUGCUCAAAGAGGCCUCGGGGCCCAUCAACUUCACCAUGUUUCUGAACCUGUUUGGGGAGAAGCUGAGCGGUACCGACGCCGAGGAGACCAUUCUUAACGCCUUCAAGAUGCUGGACCCGGACGGGAAAGGGAAAAUCAACAAGGAGUACAUCAAGCGUCUGCUGAUGUCCCAGGCUGACAAGAUGACGGCGGAAGAGGUGGACCAGAUGUUCCAGUUCGCCUCCAUCGAUGUGGCGGGCAACCUGGACUACAAGGCGCUCAGCUACGUGAUCACCCACGGGGAGGAGAAGGAGGAGUGAGACCCAGCCGGGUCAAUAAACCUGGACGCUUGGA